GUUUUUUUUUUUUUUUUGUAUUUUUAGUGGAGAUGGGGCUUUACCAUGUUGGCCAAGCUGGUCUCGAAUUCUUGACCUCAAAUGAUCCCUCACCUGGGCCUCCUAAAGUGUUGGGAUUACAGGUGUGAGCCACCUUGCCCAGCCUAAAGUUUCUUUUUUUUUGAGAUGGAGUCUUGCUCUGUCACCCAGGCCGGAGUGCAGUGGCGCUGUCUUGGCUCACUGAAACCUCUGCCUCCCAGGUUCAAGCAAUCUUCACACCUCUGCCUCCCAGGUAGCUAGGAUUACAGGCGUGUGCCACCAUGCCUGGCUAAUAUAUAAAAAAAAAUUUCUUUUGUAGAGAUGGGAUGUUGCCAUCUUACCUAGGCUAGUCUUGAACUCCUGGCCUCAAGCAGUCCUCUUACCUUGGCCCCCCAAAGUGCUGGGAUUACAGGCCUGAGCCACUGCAACCCGCUGUUUCGUUAUUCUUGACACGUUUCUGAAAACACAAGGAAAAGAGAGGUCAACGAAGAUGAUGGAUGGAAACACAGACAGCAGUAAAGAAAAUUAAGUUAUCUGAGUUAUUACGAAUGAGCAUGAUAGAUGUGAAGUGCUCCACAAAAGGAGGGGAUACUUGAGCAGAAUGUUGGGGAAUAUAAAGUAGAGAGAGGUGGGGUGAGGACUGAAAUGUCUAAUUCAGUCAGAUGUUCUAGCUAACGAUUUCUUUCUCUUGAUAUUUUUUAGAGAAAUAUGAAACGCAAUGGGAGCAGAAAUUGUUUGAAUAGGAGAAGUAGGUUUGGUUCUCGAGAAAGAGACUGGCUAAGAGAAGAUGUAAAGAGAGGCUGUGUUUACCUUUAUGGAGCAGACACUACCACUGCCACUACAACCACCACCACCUCCUCUUCCUCUUCCUCCUCCUCCUCUUCCUCUGACUUACAUCUCGUCCUUUGCACUGUAGAGACACCAGCAUCAGAAAUAUGUGCUGGAGAGGGAAGAGAAAGUCUUUAUUUACAGCUUCAUGGAGACCUGGUCAGGAGACUGGAACCUACUGAACGACCUCUUCAGAUCGUUUAUGAUUACUUAUCCAGGCUGGGAUUUGAUGAUCCUGUGCGCAUACAGGAGGAGGCUACAAAUCCUGACCUCGGCUGUAUGAUUCGAUUUUAUGGUGAAAAACCAUGCCACAUGGAUCGUUUGGAUCGAAUCCUAUUGUCUGGCAUCUAUAAUGUACGCAAGGGAAAGACCCAGCUGCAUAAGUGGGCUGAGCGCCUAGUUGUCCUCUGUGGUACCUGCCUUAUCGUUUCCUCAGUGAAGGAUUGUCAAACUGGAAAGAUGCACAUUUUGCCUCUGGUUGGUGGAAAGAUAGAAGAAGUGAAGCGACGGCAAUACUCCCUUGCUUUCAGCUCAGCAGGAGCCCAAGCUCAGACCUAUCAUGUCAGCUUCGAGACUUUGGCCGAGUACCAGCGAUGGCAACGGCAAGCAUCCAAGGUGGUGUCCCAGCGAAUCAGUACCGUGGAUCUCUCGUGUUACAGCCUCGAGGAGGUUCCUGAGCAUCUCUUCUAUAGUCAAGAUAUUACCUACCUCAACUUGCGACACAACUUCAUGCAGUUAGAAAGACCCGGAGGCCUCGAUACACUCUACAAAUUUUCUCAACUGAAGGGCCUGAACUUGUCCCAUAAUAAACUUGGGUUGUUUCCUAUAUUGUUAUGCGAGAUCUCUACCCUGACUGAGCUCAACCUUUCCUGUAAUGGAUUUCAUGACCUACCAAGUCAAAUUGGCAAUCUGCUAAAUCUUCAAACCCUCUGUCUUGAUGGCAACUUUCUGACUACUUUACCUGAAGAAUUGGGAAAUCUACAACAGCUUUCCUCCUUGGGAAUUUCCUUCAACAACUUUAGUCAAAUUCCUGAGGUUUAUGAGAAACUCACUAUGUUAGAUAGAGUGGUUAUGGCAGGAAAUUGCCUGGAAGUCCUGAACUUAGGGGUGCUGAAUAGGAUGAACCAUAUCAAGCAUGUGGAUUUAAGGAUGAACCAUUUGAAAACCAUGGUUAUUGAAAAUCUGGAGGGAAAUAAACACAUCACCCACGUGGAUCUGCGGGACAACCGACUGACUGACUUGGAUCUUAGCUCCUUAUGCAGCUUGGAACAGCUGCACUGUGGGCGGAAUCAGCUGAGGGAGCUAACACUCAGUGGCUUUUCCCUUCGGACCCUCUAUGCCAGUUCCAACAGGCUGACAGCAGUGAACGUCUAUCCAGUACCCAGCCUGCUCACUUUCUUGGAUCUCUCCCGAAACCUGCUAGAGUGUGUCCCUGACUGGGCCUGUGAAGCAAAGAAGAUAGAAGUAUUAGAUGUGAGCUAUAAUCUUCUCACAGAGGUUCCCGUGAGAAUUCUGAGUAGCUUGAGUCUUAGAAAACUGAUGCUGGGACACAAUCAUGUGCAAAACCUUCCAACACUGGUAGAGCACAUCCCCCUCGAGGUGCUGGAUCUUCAGCAUAAUGCACUCACGAGGCUGCCAGACACCCUCUUCUCCAAGGCCUUAAACAAACUAAAUAAAUUGGAGCAAUUGGAGGAACUGAACCUAAGUGGCAACAAGCUUAAAACCAUUCCCACAACCAUAGCAAACUGUAAAAGGCUGCACACCCUUGUUGCACACUCCAACAACAUCAGCAUUUUCCCAGAAAUACUGCAGUUGCCUCAGAUCCAGUUUGUAGACCUAAGUUGCAACGACUUGACAGAAAUCCUGAUUCCAGAGGCUUUGCCUGCUACAUUACAAGACCUUGACCUGACUGGAAAUACAAAUCUGGUUCUGGAACACAAGACACUGGACAUAUUUAGCCAUAUCACAACCCUGAAAAUUGAUCAGAAACCUUUGCCAACCACAGAUUCUACAGUUACGUCAACCUUCUGGAGCCAUGGACUGGCUGAGAUGGCAGGGCAGAGAAAUAAGCUGUGUGUCUCAGCACUUGCUAUGGAUAGCUUUGCAGAGGGGGUGGGAGCUGUGUAUGGCAUGUUUGAUGGAGACCGAAAUGAGGAGCUCCCGCGCCUGCUGCAGUGUACGAUGGCAGAUGUGCUUUUAGAAGAGGUACAGCAGUCAACUAAUGACACAGUUUUCAUGGCUAACACCUUCUUGGUAUCUCACAGGAAAUUAGGAAUGGCUGGCCAGAAGUUGGGCUCCUCCGCUCUCCUGUGCUACAUCCGCCCUGACACUGCCGAUCCAGCAAGUAGCUUUAGCUUGACUGUAGCCAAUGUUGGCACGUGCCAAGCAGUCCUGUGCCGAGGUGGGAAGCCAGUGCCCCUCUCUAAAGUCUUCAGCCUGGAGCAGGACCCAGAGGAGGCUCAAAGGGUGAAGGACCAAAAAGCCAUCAUCACAGAGGACAACAAAGUGAAUGGGGUAACCUGCUGUACCCGGAUGCUGGGCUGUACAUACCUCUACCCUUGGAUCCUCCCCAAGCCCCACAUAUCUUCCACUCCGCUGACCAUUCAAGAUGAGUUGCUGAUUCUGGGAAACAAAGCAUUGUGGGAACACUUGUCCUACACAGAAGCUGUCAAUGCUGUACGUCACGUACAAGACCCAUUAGCAGCUGCUAAGAAGCUGUGCACAUUAGCGCAGAGCUAUGGCUGUCAGGACAAUGUAGGGGCGAUGGUAGUUUAUUUGAAUAUUGGUGAGGAAGGCUGCACUUGUGAAAUGAAUGGGCUCACCCUCCCAGGUCCUGUGGGAUUUGCUUCAACCACCACUAUCAAGGAUGCCCCUAAGCCAGCCACUCCAUCCUCUAGCAGUGGGAUUGCCUCUGAGUUCAGCAGUGAGAUGUCCACCUCAGAGGUGAGCAGUGAAGUGGGGUCCACUGCUUCUGAUGAGCAUAAUGCUGGGGGCCUGGACACUGCCUUGCUUCCGAGGCCAGAGCGGCGCUGCAGCCUCCACCCAACACCCACCUCUGGGCUGUUUCAGCGCCAGCCUUCUUCUGCUACCUUCUCCAGUAACCAGUCUGACAACGGCCUGGACAGUGAUGAUGACCAGCCCGUUGAGGGGGUCAUAACCAAUGGCAGCAAGGUAGAGGUGGAAGUAGACAUCCACUGCUGCAGGGGGAGGGAUCUGGAGAACUCACCCCCUCUCAUAGAGAGUUCUCCUACCCUGUGUUCUGAGGAACAUGCUAGAGGGUCGUGUUUUGGGAUCCGAAGACAGAACAGUGUGAAUAGUGGCAUGCUCCUGCCAAUGAGCAAGGACAGGAUGGAGUUACAGAAGUCUCCCUCCACCUCCUGCCUCUAUGGGAAGAAACUCUCCAAUGGCUCUAUUGUGCCCCUAGAGGACAGCCUGAACCUCAUUGAAGUGGCCACAGAAGUGCCCAAGAGGAAAACUGGCUAUUUUGCUGCCCCCACUCAGAUGGAACCAGAGGACCAGUUUGUUGUGCCUCAUGACCUGGAAGAAGAAGUGAAGGAACAAAUGAAACAGCACCAGGACAGCCGGCUCGAGCCUGAGCCCCAUGAAGAGGAUCGGACCGAGCCCCCGGAGGAGUUCGACACAGCACUAUGACUGCCCCACUGGGCACAGUGUGGGAGGAGGCUGUGCAGGGUUGGGGUAGGGACUUGCUAGAGGCAUUCUGCCUCUACAUUUCUUUUUGUUUGUUCGUUUUUUUUUUGUUUGUUUGUUUUGAGACGGAGUCUUGCUCAGUCGCUCAGGCUGGAGUGCAAUGGUGGGGUCUCGGGUCACUGCAGCCUCUGUCCCUGGGUUCAAGCCAUUCUCCUGUCUCAGCCUCCCGAGUAGCUGGGAUUACAGGCACCUGCCAUUAUGCCCGGCUAAGUUUUAUUUUUUUUUUUUAGAGACGGGGUUUCACCAUGUUGGCCAGGCUGGUGUUGAACUCUUGACCUCAGGUGAUCCACCCUCCUCUGCCUCCCAAAGUGCUGUGAUUACAGGCCUCAGCCACCAUGCCCAGCCCUGCGUCUACAUUUCUAAACCAUAGCUGUGUGGGGUUGAACUCGGAGCCAAAAAGUGUGAGAGCCAUCAGGGGCUGGCUCUGGAUAAACUGGUAGCCACUAUCAGUGUUAAGUUUCACAUUUAACCUGCAUUGGAAUUCCCAGGGGUACUGGGAAGAAAGCAGCUGUUCUGUAUCAGUCCUACCACCUGCCAUUAACCCUUUCUCUCCUAGGAUCAUUUUGAGAAUUUGCCUGCCUGGGCAGGAAAGGGACUAUUUCUGUGGAGGAAAAAAGUGAAGAUUGAUUCUCUUUACUAGUUGCUGCUGAUGGAUCUCUGUGACAGAGAAAUCACCUUAUCUCAGACUAAUGGGGUGUGAUGUGACUAGUCACAUGGCUUUUCAUUCUUCUCUACGAGAAUACAGCCUAUCAAAAUGAUGUCUGUUGGAAAUGUAGAACCAAUCAAACAGAUAAUUUAUGUAUGUAAUGUAAUGAGAGCACUUUUCAUUGACUGUGAACUUUUUAUUUUUGAAUCUGCACUCGAGCCAAUCUUCUUAGAGGCAGCCCGGCACCUUCAUCCAUAGGCAGAGAGAGAACUGGGUGUUGGAGACUUAUUCGAGGGUAUAGGAAGGGCCCUGUGAAGUUGAUUUAACUUUUGGAUGUCAGACUGUGAAAGCUCCUGAGAAACUUGGGGUAAUAGGAUCUUCUUUUGGGGAUGAAAAUGGGGAAGGCGUGAGGACCUAGACUACUUCUCCCUAGAUCAGAAAAAGAGAAUUACCCCUUGACAAAUAUGAUACCUGCUAGGUAUUUCCCAGGGAAAUUUAGGGAUUGGCGUCUUUCCCUAGCAUGUGGAGGAAUUGGCAGACAGCUUCCUAAGGGCGGGGAGCGGGGGCCCAAGGCUGACACUGCUUGCAUCCACGUGACCUUAAGUUAUGGCAGAUGACUCUGAAACGGACUGAGGCCAAUGAGAACAGAUGGAUGGAGCACUCAGGUUAGACUUGUUCCUUCUCCUAUGCUGGAGGAGAGGGAUGGUUCUCUAGAAUGUUGGAGGUGAGUUGAGAGCUCGCCUCUUGAAUGUUGAACAGUGUACUCUUCUGAAAACUGCAUAUUCACUUUAUGUGGUUUCAGAAUACUGGGCUCAAUACUAACAUAAGAAAGACACUUCAUUGAGAAAUUCUUAAGCUUACAGAAAACCUAUACUCUUUGCACAUUCCACAUAACCCUAGCAAAAUGCAGUUUCUUCAUACUUCUGUCACUUUUUCCAUUGGAAGAUUUGCUUAGGAAAAUUAAUUCCUAUUUAUUCCCACAAAAUGUUGGCAUUGCUUGAUUUUACCCAAUGGGGAAUGUGCUUUGAAUUUUUGGAACACUUUUACAAUUAAAAAUAAAGUAGGGCCAUUUUUAAUUUGUUUCAUCAGAAACUAUGUUAAAGAGAGGGUUAAAUAUAAAUAUAUUUUCGUGUGUAUUUUUGGGAAGAUUUUUGUUCAAAGCAAUAGUCAAAAUCAGAUGACCUGUCCAUAAUAAUUAUGUGUCUUCAUCUUCUCAGAGGCCCCAUGCUCAUAUGCACGUGUCAUUGGGAUACACUCUUGGGGGAUUUGGUACACUCUAAUGGAUGUCUAAUGUUCAACCCCUCGAGAAUCUGAACUUGAGUCCCCAGAUUGUCAAACUACUGGUCAGCUAUUGAGAAUUUUAGAACUCAGGUCUUUGAUUUGAAGUAGGGAACAUAGUGGCUCACACAGAGUUUAGGUGCUGUUAGAAAGAUGGGAACAAGAGUGUUUUGCCACCUUAUUUUUAUAUGGGAAAUUUUUUUUAAUGAAGAAAAAAUGAAAAUGAAAUAACAGGAUGAUAGUGAUGAGUGAUGUAAAACAUCUUACUUAGAUGGCAGAACCUUCGGGUUGUAGAAUAGUGAUGUCUAAAAAUUAAAGUUAUUUUGGGAAUACACCACUUUAAUAGUAUAGUCUUAUAAAAAUUAUUCAUUAUGGUGAACCCUUCUUGUCUGCUAUUCGUUUCCCAACCUACUUAUUGGAACCACCUCAAAACCCAGUUCUGAAAUGACCUUACCAAAAGUAAAUGUAUUUAUUUUUUAGUCAGCAGAACUCUGUAAUUCCAAAUGUUGUUCUGUGUGGUAGAAUUUUUUUUCAGGAACCAUUAGGUUGUAUUGAAAAUCUUUGUUAUAGGCGAUACCAAAACUGAUUAUUCUUUUUUGCAGUCUGCUUUAAUUCAUGUCCUUCUGCAGUUGCUCUGUAUUAAAACAGGGUAAAAAGGCCAUAGCCCAUUAUGAAAAAUAUAAUACAAAACUCUUUGACCUAUGAGGUAACUUACAGACAUUGUGUUUUCUAAACAGGCUGUCAGUGAAAGCCCGUAUCUGUCUCCAGGUGAAUGUAAUUUACUUCCGAGUACUUUACCCAGAGGAUGUGUUCCCCAGGUGGGCAGAGUACAGUUGAUCUCUAGCACAGACAGAGAUUCUGGCCUCUGCAUAUUCUCAGGUCUCUGUGUGUACCUCCCAUUGAGUAGAGAAGCUUAAGAUAAUUUCUGAGAGAAGAACACUGCUGAUUGUGGGAGCAGUUUAGGAGUCCAUGGAAGAAAGAAAAAUACAUGUGUCUUGGCAGCCAUGGUGUAUUUUUGUCCAAAUGGAUUGGAAGGAUAUUUGAAUAUUUGAAUGUUGGUAUGACAUAAAGCUGCAGUGCACUAUAGAGUCAAGUCAUUGAAUUACCACUCCUGAUACAGGGCUUUAUUGUACUACUGUGAAGUGUAUGUGUGCAAUACAUUGGUGAGUUCAUUUACUGGUGUACGGAAGAGCCAGCAGGAGCAGCGUGGUCAUUGCUGGGUGCUAUUACAGUUGCUUGUAGUGAGUGCUGUUUUCCAGGAGAUGGAGCCAGUUGGGUGUGGCAGAUCUACUGAAUAUCAAAUGAUGCUCUUCUUCCCAUGUAGACCUUCAGCAAAAGCCGGUACUUGGAAGCCACAGGCUCACCUUCUCUAUCUAUCCAAUAAUUAUUAAUGAAGAGACCUCCAUAAGGGAGCAGCUGGCUGUUAUCGAUAAAUGUACCAAUUAUUAAAUAAUUAGUCUCCAAGCCAUUCAGUGAUGUCUUCAGCAUCACUAUAGGACUGUCUAGUGUCACUUUUUACUUCCUUCUGGGUGGAGGCUUUCCGACUCCCAAUCAUGAAGGCAAGUUAAUCUUUCCAGUUAGUGACUUUUGCCCCAUAGUUGGGGUAAGCACUUCCUAGAUUGAGAAAAAGCAGCUACAGUCAAUCCUGCUCUGUUUGCCUCAUUUGGUGAUCAGUCAGUCACACAUAAGUUCCUUGUAUUCUAAAUUUCAUGCACUUCUCCCAGAUGCUAUAGGGUUUUCUCUCACUGUUGCCAGUGGAUGUCAUCCAGACAGUGGGCUCAUAUCUUACGGUUUUGUGCAAUCAUUGUCGUAUUGUAGUCUUAAGACUCAUUAUAGUGUAUUUUUGAUAUUUUUGAAAUGUGUUAAAUUUUUUAAUUCAAUAAUAUGAGCCAGAGCAUGUUGCAGCAAAUCUAUUGUUUGUAAAAAUAACAAUAACAAUAAUAAAUAAAAUAAAGUGGAAUCUUUUUCAUGGCUUUGUUUUAAAA